AGGGCAGCAAGUAAUUACUAAGUUGUUUUAUGGAGAAACCAAUGUUGUCACCAUACCACACACAGCUAUGUUACAGCCCUGAUGACACCACCUACAAGUCAUUUAGUCUCAGUCACUUCCUAGUGAAGCUCUAGCUUCCAUUUAAUCAGAGACAGUUUGGGAAAGAAGGAGGUGACAUACAACCAGAGUCGUAAUUGGAAAAUAGCCCAGGCAGUGUUCCUUGUGAUUUUAUGUUGUUUUCAUCAACUUGGUGUUUGGAAAUAGACGUCAGUUAGUGACAUGUGUAGCAGGCAUAGAGGAAAGAAUGAACUUUGAAACCAGAAUUCUUGUGUUCAGAUCCCAGGUCUGCAGCCCCCUCGUUGUGGGCCUGUGGCAGAUUAGUGGUCCCUCCGAGUCUCGGUGUCUUCAUUUUUAACAUGGAGACGACCAGAGGGAAACUCCUGGCUGGGUAAGGCCCCCCAAGAGAGAGGCUUCAGCUGCAGGUGGCUUUCUUUGGCCAAAGUCCUGGGAAGGCCUGGACGACACUCAAGAAAAAGCAGUGACAAACAGACGACGUGCUGAGCUGCCAGCUUAGUGGAAGCUCUGCUCUGGGUGGAGAGCAGCCUCGCUUUGGUGACGCACAGUGCUGGGACCCUCCAGGAGCCCCGGGAUUGAAGGAUGGUGGCGGCCGUCCUGCUGGGGCUGAGCUGGCUCUGCUCUCCCCUGGGAGCUCUGGUCCUGGACUUCAACAACAUCAGGAGCUCUGCUGACCUGCAUGGGGCCCGGAAGGGCUCACAGUGCCUGUCUGACACGGACUGCAAUACCAGAAAGUUCUGCCUCCAGCCCCGCGAUGAGAAGCCGUUCUGUGCUACAUGUCGUGGGUUGCGGAGGAGGUGCCAGCGAGAUGCCAUGUGCUGCCCUGGGACACUCUGUGUGAACGAUGUUUGUACUACGAUGGAAGAUGCAACCCCAAUAUUAGAAAGGCAGCUUGAUGAGCAAGAUGGCACACAUGCAGAAGGAACAACUGGGCACCCAGUCCAGGAAAACCAACCCAAAAGGAAGCCAAGUAUUAAGAAAUCACAAGGCAGGAAGGGACAAGAGGGAGAAAGUUGUCUGAGAACUUUUGACUGUGGCCCUGGACUUUGCUGUGCUCGUCAUUUUUGGACGAAAAUUUGUAAGCCAGUCCUUUUGGAGGGACAGGUCUGCUCCAGAAGAGGGCAUAAAGACACUGCUCAAGCUCCAGAAAUCUUCCAGCGUUGCGACUGUGGCCCUGGACUACUGUGUCGAAGCCAAUUGACCAGCAAUCGGCAGCAUGCUCGAUUAAGAGUAUGCCAAAAAAUAGAAAAGCUAUAAAUAUUUCAAAAUAAAGAAGAAUCCACAUUGCAUUUGA